GUCCCCGGGCCAAGAUGGCUGCGCGGUGCUCCACACGCUGGUUGCUGGUGGUUGUGGGGACCCCGCGGCUGCCGGCUAUAUCGGGUAGAGGGGCCCGGCCGCCCAGGGAGGGCGUGGUGGGGGCAUGGCUGAGCCGCAAGCUGAGCGUCCCCGCCUUUGCGUCUUCCCUGACCUCUUGCGGCCCCCGAGCGCUGCUGACAUUGAGACCUGGUGUCAGCCUUACAGGAACAAAACAUAACCCUUUCAUUUGUACUGCCUCCUUCCACACGAGUGCCCCUUUGGCCAAAGAAGAUUAUUAUCAGAUAUUAGGAGUGCCUCGAAAUGCCAGCCAGAAAGAGAUCAAGAAAGCCUAUUAUCAGCUUGCCAAGAAGUAUCACCCUGACACAAAUAAGGAUGAUCCCAAAGCCAAGGAGAAGUUCUCCCAGCUGGCAGAAGCCUAUGAGGUUUUGAGUGAUGAGGUGAAGAGGAAGCAGUACGAUGCCUACGGCUCUGCAGGCUUCGAUCCUGGGGCCAGCGGCUCCCAGCAUAGCUACUGGAAGGGAGGCCCCACUGUGGACCCCGAGGAGCUGUUCAGGAAGAUCUUUGGCGAGUUCUCAUCCUCUUCAUUUGGAGAUUUCCAGACCGUGUUUGAUCAGCCUCAGGAAUACUUCAUGGAGUUGACAUUCAAUCAAGCUGCAAAGGGGGUCAACAAGGAGUUCACCGUGAACAUCAUGGACACGUGUGAGCGCUGCAACGGCAAGGGGAACGAGCCCGGCACCAAGGUGCAGCAUUGCCACUACUGUGGCGGCUCCGGCAUGGAAACCAUCAACACAGGCCCUUUUGUGAUGCGUUCCACGUGUAGGAGAUGUGGUGGCCGCGGCUCCAUCAUCAUAUCGCCCUGUGUGGUCUGCAGGGGAGCAGGACAAGCCAAGCAGAAAAAGCGAGUGAUGAUCCCUGUGCCUGCAGGAGUCGAGGAUGGCCAGACCGUGAGGAUGCCUGUGGGAAAAAGGGAAAUUUUCAUUACGUUCAGGGUGCAGAAAAGCCCUGUGUUCCGGAGGGACGGCGCAGACAUCCACUCCGACCUCUUUAUUUCUAUAGCUCAGGCUCUUCUUGGGGGUACAGCCAGAGCCCAGGGCCUGUACGAGACGAUCAACGUGACGAUCCCCCCUGGGACUCAGACAGACCAGAAGAUUCGGAUGGGUGGGAAAGGCAUCCCCCGGAUUAACAGCUACGGCUACGGAGACCACUACAUCCACAUCAAGAUACGAGUUCCAAAGAGGCUAACGAGCCGGCAGCAGAGCCUGAUCCUGAGCUACGCCGAGGACGAGACAGAUGUGGAGGGGACGGUGAACGGCGUCACCCUCACCAGCUCUGGUGGCAGCACCAUGGAUAGCUCCGCAGGAAGCAAGGCUAGGCGUGAGGCUGGGGAGGACGAGGAGGGAUUCCUUUCCAAACUUAAGAAAAUGUUUACCUCAUGAUAUCCCAGCCGAGGAAAAAGAUCCACUGGAAACUAGGCCGGGAAGCAGCAGCCCCUCCAAGGGCCAGGGCACCUGGGAGACGGGAGGAUUCCAGAACAGCAGCACUGAGCUCCCACCCGCAGAGCCUCUGGACGGCCUUGGCAACAGCAAAAUCAUGGGACAACACCUCUCUCCACGGAAAGGUCACAGUGGACAGCCCGGGCAGUAGGAUGCAGCCCCAGAGGCUGGUGGCAGUUUCCUGUCCAUUGGUAGGUGACGGCCCCUGGCUCAGGCAGAGGGAGAUGGUUAGACUCUUGCAGGGCUAAAACUCUAAUUUGGAAUUGAAUAUUGUGGAUAUCUUAGUUAAAGGCCAUGCUUACAGCUUAGAAAUGAAGCCUUAAGCUGCAUCAAGUUACGAAGUGAUUAAUUUCCUUCUCAGCAAACCUCCGGGAGGUUCCAGAAUGAGUUCUUCCUGACAGGUUGUCUUCACUGGGAGCGUGGGGCCCCCAGGCCCCACCAGCACCGUCCUCCCCUAAUGAGGGGCCCUGCCGAGGCAUCAGCUGCUCUGCUCAGUUAGUUUUUAUUCCCGGGGUACCAAGCAGCUGCACAGUCGGUGCCUGGGAGGCACGUAGAGGCCCAGAGAGUCCCUGGGGGUUCUGCUCUGACCGUGUGGGUGGUGAUCCUUGUCAGGAUGUACAGUCCUUGCUCCCACCCCAUCCGGGAUGGCCGCCUGUCCCUGACUAUUGAGUCCUGUUGUUGUAAGCCAGGCAUGGAGGGCUCCUGCCCUUCUGCUGAGCCACAGCCCAUUGCAGCACUGUGCUGGCCAGACUUCAGCUGCCUUGGGAACUGAAGCCCUGCCACUGUUGCUAGUCAGGGGCUUGGUUCUCCCACUUACACUGUUGACAUCUAUUUUCUGAAGUGUGUUUAAAUUAUUCAGUGCUAAUCAUUGUUUUUUCCUUUGUAAAUGUUGAUUCAGAAAAGGAAAGCACAGGCUAAGCAGUUGAAGGUUCCCCACCAUUCAGUGAGAGCAGAACCCCCAUUCCCCAGCCUCUGCUGGUAGCAUGUCGCAGUUUCCAUGUGUUUCAGGAUCUUCGGGCUGUCGUUAGACAGGUUAAUGAAGAACACUUCUCAACAGUUUCCUUUUUGUUUUCCUUUAUAAUUCACUAAAAUAAAGCAUCUAUUAGUGUCUGAUUUAGGAAUGUAAAAUGAUUCUGUAUUAAUGUAAAUAAGAUUAUCUAUUGCAAAAAGAUAUUUCAAACCUAAA